GAUUACAGUCUUGAGCCACCAUGCCCAGCCAAAAAAGAAGUCUUAUUGUUAGGUGUUGUUCAAGUAUGUGACAAGCCAGGAUCCCAACCUGAGUCAUCUGACUUCAAAGUCCACAUUCUUAACUGCCAUGUUACACUACCUUCCAUAUUAUGAUCCUGGCACCUGGUAUACUCUGUCAAUUUACAAAUGACCAUAUAUGUGGAACGCAGUAGGCGAUUUAAGAAACAGCAUAGGAUUGGGCCAGGCGCGGUGGCUCACGCCUGUAAUCCCAGCACUUUGGGAGGUGGAGGCGGGUGGAUCACGAGGUCAGGAGAUCGAGACCAUCCUGGCCAACAUGGUGAAACCCCGUCUCUACUAAAAAUACAAAAAUUAGCCGGGCAUGGUGGUGUGCGCCUGUAAUCCCAGCUACUCAGGAGGCUGAGGCAGGAGAAUCACUUGAACCUGGGAGGCGGAGGCUGCAGUGAGCUGAGAUCAUGCCACUGCACUCCAGCCUGGGCGACAGAGUGAGACUAUUUAAAAAAAAAAAAAAAAAAAAGUGUAGGGUUACAUAUGCCUAAUACAGGAAAGAAGAUCCAAAGGGGCCUGACAAAAUAAACCUUAAAAUAAAAAUCAGAUGAUGCUCAAUGAGAAACAACUAGCAUAGAGUUACACUAAAGACUGUUCUUUCCCCUAUACACAAUCACAGAUUAAAAGAGGGUGCAAGAUACCUUUUUUUUUUUUUUUUUUUGAGAUAGGGUCUCAUUCUAUCUCCCAGGCUGGAAUACAGUGGCGCAAUCCCAGCUCACUACAGCCUGAACUCCCGUGCUCAAAUAAUCCUCUUACCUUGAACUCCUGGGCUUAAGCGAGGCUGCCUCAGCCUUUUAAAUAGCUGGGAUUACAGGAAACGGGCCGCCACCACCACCACGCCCAGCUAAUUUUAAAUUUUUUCUGUAGACAGGGUCUCCCUUUGAUGCUGUGAACUCCUAGCCUUAAAUAAUCCUCCUGCUUAGGCCUCCCAAAGCACUUGGAUUAUGGUCAGCCCAUUCUGUGCCUGGCCCCUUACACCAUUCUGAAAAGGAAUCUCAAGAGCUAGAAAUCUCAGUGCUGGGUAGGUAAACAAUAAUGGAUCAAACCCACUGGGAGAGAGGUCUUGGGAAGCCCUAGAUGACACUCCCACCAUCCUUGUCUCCAUCAUGCCUAGCAUGGCUCACAGUGCUCAAAUGGGGGCAUAAACAACUGUGGAGGAAAUAAUCACUAGUUGGAUCAAUGUAAAAUAAUGCUUAUGAUGCACAUAAAGUACUAGAACUGCUGGGCCUGAAAAAUAUUUUGAAAUGUAAUGAAUUUCUCCUACAUAAAAGAUGUAAAAAAGGUGGAGGAUUCAGUUAGAAAAGCAUAUGGAGCAACAGCACACUGAAGAGCCUGGACUUUAUCUUUUAGUCUAGGCAUACCCAGAAGUAAAAAGACUCAGAAAGCAAAAAAGCAUAUAUUAGAGAUAAUAUAAGCAGUACGAAAAAAAAAAAAAAGUUGGCCAGGUGCUGUGGCUCACGCUUGUAAUCCGAGCACUCUGGGAGGCAGAGGCGGGUGAAUCACUUGAAGUCAGGAGUUCGAGACCAGCUUGGCCAACAUGGUGAAACUCCGUCUCUACUAUAAAUACAAAAAAAAACUGGCCAGGUGCGGUGGCUCACGCCUGCAAUCCCAGCACUUUGGGAGGCUGAGGCGGGUGGAUCACGAGGUCAGGAGUUCAAGACCAGCCUGGCUAAGAUGGUGAAACCCCAUCUCUACUAAAAAUACAAAAAUUAGCCGCACUCCGUCUCAAAAAAAAAAAAUUAGCCAGGCGUGGUGCCAGGCGCCUGUAAUCCCAGCUACUUGGGAGGCUGAGGCAGGAGAAUUGCUUGAACCCGGAAGGUGGAGGUUGCAGUGAGCCGGGAUCACGCCACUGCACUCCAGCCUGGGAGACAGAGUGAGACUCUGUCUCAAACAAAACAAAACAAAACAAAAAAACUUCUAAGUCAAGUAAGGUUCAAACACUAGAAGGCAGUGAAAUACGAAUUUGGGGCAAAAGAUUGCGGACGACGUCAGACUUUGAGAAACUUAACUGUGAAUCUGCGUCUGAGGUAAAUACAUUUCACUGUUUCCGUUUCUGCAGCUCUUCCUAAGGAAUGGAAGCCCAGACUGCCUGGGAGGCAGGAGACCUCGUUUCCAGCUCCCGGCCCUUACUGCCGCUGCAAAUCCUAGACUGGCUAGAGACCAUUCGCUGCAGCGGACGUCGGAAAACGAGACCUCGCAGUUCAGGAGGCAGGAAAAAGACAUGCCCGCGCCCUCAUCCCAAUAGCCCAGGCCCAAGCCAGCCCGGAGAGAAAAGACCUGAGGAGGUGGCCCUGGGGCUGCACCACCGCCUCCCAGCACUGGGAAGAGCCCUGGGGCACAGCAUUCAGCAACGAGCGACCUCCACAGCCAAGACUUGGUGGGACAGAUAUGAAGAGUUUGUUGGACUCAACGAGGUUCGAGAGGCCCAGGGAAAGGUGACAGAGGCUGAGAAAGUGUUCAUGGUGGCUCGAGGGCUUGUCCGAGAGGCUCGGGAGGACUUGGAAGUUCACCAGGCCAAGCUGAAGGAGGUGAGGGACCGCUUGGACCGUGUCUCCAGGGAGGACAGUCAGUACUUGGAACUGGCUACUCUCGAGCACAGGAUGCUGCAGGAGGAGAAGAGGCUUCGCACAGCCUAUCUGCGUGCAGAAGACUCUGAGCGAGAGAAGUUCUCCCUCUUCUCUGCAGCUGUGCGGGAAAGUCAUGAGAAGGAGCGCACAAGGGCUGAGAGGACCAAGAACUGGUCCCUCAUUGGCUCAGUCCUGGGGGCCCUGAUUGGUGUGGCUGGCUCCACCUAUGUGAACCGUGUGCGACUACAGGAGCUGAAGGCUUUACUCCUGGAGGCGCAGAAGGGGCCUGUGAGUCUCCAAGAGGCCAUUCGAGAACAGGCGUCUAGCUACUCCCGCCAGCAGAGGGACCUCCACAAUCUCAUGGUGGACCUGAGGGGCCUGGUACAUGCUGCUGGGCCAGGGCAGGACUCUGGGUCACAGGCAGGUAGUCCCCCGACCAGAGACAGAGAUGUAGAUGUCCUUUCAGCUGCCUUGAAAGAGCAGCUUAGUCAUUCCAGGCAAGUCCAUUCAUGUCUAGAAGGCUUACGAGAGCAGCUUGAUGGCCUAGAAAAGACUUGUAGCCAAAUGGCUGGGGUGGUUCAGCUUGUAAAGUCUGCAGCACACCCAGGCCUGGUGGAACCAGCAGACGGGGCUAUGCCCAGCUUCUUGCUGGAGCAGGGGAGCAUGAUCUUGGCACUGUCAGACACGGAGCAGAGACUAGAAGCCCAAGUCAACAGGAACACCAUCUAUAGCACCCUGGUCACCUGUGUGACAUUUGUGGCCACACUGCCUGUGCUCUACAUGCUAUUCAAAGCCAGCUAACCCCUGGCCCCUCCUCCAGAGGGUCUGAGGCAAUAGCUGUGAAUGUGGAUUUAAGUAGAGAAUCGUAGCAAUGAAGCGAGCCUUUGGGGGCAUGUACAACCUCAAUCUGAAGGAGCAGUAUCUGUGUGGCUCACCAGCAGGCAUGCUUCGCUUUGUAGACAAGGUUCAUUUACAUUAAUUAUCAAAACUUUGUGCUAAUGUCCAAUUAAAAUAUCCUGAGUUUUAUUAUUUAAAA